UGUUGAUAGCCCAUUGUGCAAAAUAAGUGAUAAAAUUCAAAGUUCUUGAUGGUGCUGAGGUCCAGUGGGAAAAACAAGAAAACUAAGAUGUUGGAGAGUAAUUACACCAUGCCAACUGAGUUCCUAUUUGUUGGAUUCACAGAUUAUCUACCUCUCAGAGUCACACUGUUCUUGGUAUUCCUUCUGGUAUAUACAUUAACUAUGGUCGGAAAUAUACUCUUAAUAAUUCUAGUUAAUAUUAAUUCAAGCCUUCAAAUUCCCAUGUAUUAUUUUCUUAGCAACUUAUCUUUCUUAGACAUCAGCUGUUCUACAGCAAUCACUCCUAAAAUGCUGGCAAACUUCUUGGCAUCCAGGAAAAGCAUCUCUCCUUAUGGGUGUGCACUACAAAUGUUUUUCUUCGCUUCUUUUGCUGAUGCUGAGUGCCUUAUCCUGGCAGCAAUGGCUUAUGACCGCUAUGCAGCCAUCUGCAACCCACUGCUCUAUACUACACUGAUGUCUAGGAGAGUCUGUGUCUGCUUCAUUGUGUUGGCAUAUUUCAGUGGAAGUACAACAUCACUGGUCCAUGUGUGCCUCACAUUCAGGCUGUCAUUUUGUGGCUCCAAUAUCGUCAAUCAUUUUUUCUGUGAUAUCCCACCUCUUCUGGCUUUAUCAUGUACAGACACUCAGAUCAACCAGCUUCUGCUCUUUGCUUUGUGCAGCUUCAUCCAGACCAGCACUUUUGUGGUAAUAUUUAUUUCUUACUUCUGCAUCCUCAUCACUGUGUUGAGCAUCAAGUCCUCAGGUGGCAGAAGCAAAACAUUCUCCACUUGUGCUUCCCACCUCAUAGCAGUCACCUUAUUCUAUGGAGCGCUCCUGUUUAUGUACUUACAGCCCACCACUAGCUAUUCCCUAGACACUGAUAAGGUGGUGGCAGUGUUUUAUACUGUUGUAUUUCCCAUGUUUAAUCCAAUAAUUUAUAGUUUCAGAAACAAGGAUGUGAAAAAUGCUCUCAAAAAGCUAUUAGAAAGAAUUGGAUAUUCAAAUGAAUGGUAUUUAAAUCGUUUAAGAAUAGUCAAUAUCUAACUUACCCUUCCAAUCUCAUAAACAGCAAUUAUGCCAUGAACAUCUUAUGUGUUAACUAUUUUAAAUUUAUCACAUUUUCAGAAAUAAAGAUAACUUGUUAUACUCAGUGCAUUAAAAUGCUUCAUCCUCUCUUCCAAAAAUGUUCUCUCCACAAUUCUACUCUAUAAAACAUUACCUAAUUAAACAUAGUCAUUAUUUAUAUCCAAUUAGUGUUUCUAAAAUGCUUUGUACAUUGAUUCUGUUCUUUACGAUGUUGUAUUGAAGGUAAAUAUUGACUUUUCAGUCAAUCAAUCGGUAUUAGAAGCUACUUGGCAGCAGAGCAUGUGUAUAUUGGCUUGUUUUUUCCACCACCUGUUUGGCACCUGGUAUACUGCAUGUCUUCCUUAUCUGUGUGUUUAGGCCAUUUAUGCAUAGAGUUCCAUUAUUGGAACACUAAGCAUCCUACUGCUCAAGGUCAUCGCCAAGGUCUGAUUUCAAAAAUUCAAAAUAUUGUAACCUCAGACAUAAAUUUAAGUAUGGAUGGAGGGAUGGAUAGAUGGAUAGAUAGAUGAAUGACUGGGAAAAUACAGCCUUAUUUUAUUUGGACAGUGAGUCUAUAUUUGUACUCACAAAGCAUUUGUCAAUAGAGAUAUUUUAUAAUACCAAUAAUCUGUUAGGGAUACUGAUGGUGGUUUCACUGGUUCUCAAGAAAUUAGAAGACAUGUAGCAAUAGUCUCAUUAUUAUUAAGUCAGAAUGAAGAUACAUCACAUUGUCUUUGGGCUAAGUUGAUUACUGCAAGAAAUUCCCUACUUUUUCAUUCAGAGUGGGUAAUUGUGAAAAACAAGUUUGUGAAUACUAUCAAGAUUAUAAACUGUAGAAUUUCCUAAUUAUUUAUAUUCAUGUUGCUAACAUAGUCUUUGAGGCUCUAUCUUCAAGAAGAGGUGAAAAUUACACUGAUCUUUUAUUCUGUAAAUUUACAAUGCAAGGCAAUUAAAGUAUAAACAAUUUUUACUCUGUAAUCGAUUUUGAUAAUUAAAUUAUCAGAUUUUUUGUGGUUUAUUCUGAUCUUUCAGUCUGAAGUCUCUAUUUACUUUUUGUCUUAUUUUGACAAAGUUAAAGUGAUACACCAUGUACAUGUGAAAUAAAAAAGUGUGCAUUUUGUAAUAAUUAUGAAAAUAUAAAUGGUUGGAUUAGUUAUAUUGAAUUUAACCUUGGACAUGGAGACAAUAAGAUAGCACCUAAUGAAAUGGAUUGUUUUGAGUAUUAAGUAAAGUUAUAUAUGUAAAAUUACUGGUAUAUGUAUAUGAUUUGAAAAUUAAAUAAUCUAAUAUUUAUAGACAUACCAUGAAGAUACUGUGGGUUCUCUUCUAGAUCACUACAAUAAAGCAACUGACGCAGUAAAGUGUCACACAAAUUUUUAGAUUUCUCAGUGCAUAUCAUAGUUAUGUUUGGUGGCUGGCAAGAUGGUCAAAUAGGAGAUGCUCCAGUCUGCUGCUCCCAGCAAGAUCAACAGAGAAGGUGGGUGAUUUCUGCAUUUCCAACUGAGGUACCUGGCUCAUCUCAUUGGGACUGGUUAGACAGUGGGUGCAGCCCAUGGUGGGUGAGCAGAAGCAGGGUGGGGUGUUGCUUCACCCGGGAAGCACAAAGGGUUGGCAAACUCCCUCCACUAGCCAAGGGAAGCCAUGAAGGACUGUGCCAUGAGGAACGGGUGCACUCUGGCCCAGAUACUAUGCUUUUCCCAUCGUCUUCACAACACACGGACCAGGAGAUUCCCUUGGGUGCCUACAUCACCAGCUCCCUGGGAUUGAAGCACAAAACUCGGUGGCUGUUUGGGCAGGCACUGAGCUAGCUGCAGGAGUUUUCUUCAUACCCCAGUGGCACCUGGAAUGCCAGCGAGACAGAACCAUUCACUCCCCUGGAAAGGGGGCUGAAGCCAGGGAGCCAAGUGGUCUAGCUCAGCAGAUCCCACCCCCAUGGAGCCCAGCAAGCUAAGAUCCACUGGCUUGAAAUUCUUCCUGCAAGCAUAGCAGUCUGAAGUUGACCUGGGAUGCUCGAGCUUGGUUGGAGGAGGAGAGUCCGCCAUUGCUGAGGCUUCAGUAGGCAGUUUUCCCCUCAUAGUGUAAACAAAGCUGCCAGGAAGUUUGAACUGGGUGGAGCCCACCGCAGCACUGCAAAACCUCUGUAGCCAGACUGCCUCUCUAGAUUCCUCCUCUCUGGGCAGGGGAUCUCUAAAAAAAAGGCAGCAGCCCCAGUUAGGGGCCUAGAGAUAAAACCCCCAUCCCCCUGAGACAGAGCACCUUAAGGAAGGGAUGGCUGUGGGUGCAGCUUCAGCAGAUUUAAAUGUCCCUGCCUGCUGGCUCUAAGGAGAGCAGCAUACCUCCCAGCACAUCGUUCAAGCUCUCCUAAGAGAUAGACUCCUGCAUCAAGUGGGUCCUUGACCCCGUGACUCUUGACUGGGAGACACCUUCCAGUAGGGGUUGACAGAUACCUCAUAGGAGAGAGCUCCAGCUGGCAUCUCACAGGUGUGCCUCUAGGAUGAAGCUUCCAAAGGAAGGAACGGGCAGCAAUCUUUACUGUUCUGCAGCCUUCGCAGGCAAACAGGGUCUGGAGUGGAUCUCCAGCAAACUCCAGCAGACCUGCAGCAGAGGGGCCUGACAAUUAAAAGGAAAACUAAGGAAUAGCAUCAAUAUCAACAAAAAGGACGUCCACUCAGAAACUCCACCACCAACAUCAAAGACCAAAGGUAGAUAAAUGCAUGAUGGUGAGGAAAAACCAAUGCAAAAAGGCUGAAAAUUUCUAAAACCAGACAUCUCUUCUCCCACAAAGGAUCACAAUUCCACGCCAGCAAGGAAACAAAACUGGACAGAGAAUGAGUUUGAUGAAUUGAUGGAAGUAAUUGGGUAAUAACAAAUAGAAGAAUUGGGUAAUAUCAAACUCCUCUGAGCUAAAGGAGCAUGUCCUAACUCAAUGCAAAGAAGCUAAGAACCUCGAAAAAUGGUUAGAGGAAUUGCUAAUUAGAAUAACUGGUUUGAAGAGAACAUAAAUAACCUGAUGGAGCUGAAAAACACAGCACGAGAACUUCAUGAAGCAUACACAAGCAUCAAUAGCCAAAUCGAUCAAACAGAAGGAAGGAUAUCAGAGAUUGAAGAUCAACUUAAUGAAAUAAAGCUUGAAGACAAGAUUAGAGAAAAAAGAAUGCAAAGAAAUGAACAAAGCCCCCAGGGAUUAUGGGACUAUGUGAAAAGAGCAAACAUAUAUUUGAUUGGUGUACCUGAAAGUGAGGGGGAGAAUGGAACCAACUUGGAAAACACUCUUCAGGAUAUCAUCCAGGAGAAACUCCCCAACCUAACAAGACAGGCCAACAUUCAAAUUCAGGAAAUACAUGUAACACCACAAAGAUACACCUCAAGAAGAGCAACCCCCAGACACAUAAUCAUCAGAUUCACCAAGGUGGAAAUGAAGGAAAAAAUGUUAAGGUGUUAAGGACAGCCAGAGAGAAAGCUCACAUUACCCACAAAGGGAAGCCCAUCAGACUAACAGCGGCUGUCUCAGCAGAAACCCUAUAAGCCAGAAGUGAGUGGGGGCCAAUAUCCAACAGUCUUAAAGAAAAGAAUUUUAAAUGCAGAGUUUCAUAUUCAGCCAAACUAAGCUUCAUGAGUGGAGGGAAAUAAAAUCCUUUACAGAAAAGCAAAUGCUGAGAGAUUUUGUCACCACCAGGCCUGCUUUACAAGAGCUCCUGAAGGAAGCACUAAACAUGGAAAGGUACAACUGGUAACAGCCACUGCAAAAAAAACAAAUUUUAAAGAACAUUGACACUACGAAGAAACCACAUCAGCUAAUGGGCAAAAUAACCAGCUAGCAUCAUAAUGACAGGAUCAAAUUCACACAUAACAAUAUUAACCUUAAAUGUAAAUGGGCUGAAAGCCCCAGUUAAAAGCCACAGACUGGCAAAUUGGAUAGAGUCAAGACCGAUUGGUGUGCUGUAUUCAGGAGACCGAUCUCAUGUGCAAAGCAUACAUAGGCUCAAAAUAACGGGAUGGAGGAAUAUUUACCAAGCAAAUGGAUAGCAAAUAAAGAAAAAAGAAAAAAAAAACAACAAAGCACAGGGGUUGUAAUCCUAGUCUCUGAUAAAACAGACUAUAACCAAAAAAGAUCAAAAGAGAUAAAGAAGGCAAUACAUAAUGGUAAAAGGAUCAAUGCAACAAGAAGAGCUAACUAUACUAAAUAUAUAUGUACCCAAUACAAGAGCACCCAAAUUCAUAAAGCCAGUUCUUAGAGAUCUAUGAAGAGACUUAGACUAACACACAAAAAUAGUGGGAGACUUUAACACCCCACAGUCAACAUUAGACAGACCAAGACAGAAAAUUAACAAGGAUAUUCAGGACUUGAACUCAGCUCUGGACCAAGCAGACCUAAUAGACCUCUACAGAACUCUACACCCCAAAUCAAUAGAAUAUACAUUAUUCUCAGCACCACAUUGCAUUUAUUCUAAAAUUGACCACAAUAUUGCAAGUAAAAUACUCCUCAGCAAAUGCAAAACAAUGGAAAUCAUAACAGUCUCUCAGACCACAGUGCAAUCAAAUUAGAACUCAGGAUUAAGAAACUCACUCAAAACCACACAUCUACAUGGAAACUGAACAACCUGCUCAUGAAUGACUACUGGGUAAAUAAUGAAAAUAAAGCAGAAAUAAAUAAGUUAUUUGAAACCAAUGAGAACAAAGACACAAGGUAUCAGAAUCUCUGGGACAUAGCUAAAGCAGUGUUUAGAGGAAAAUUCACAGUACUAAAGGCCCACAAGAGAAAGCAGGAAAGAUCUAAAAUCAACACCCUAACAUCACAAUUAAAAGAACUAGAUAAACAAGAACAAACAAAUUCAAAAGCCUCAGAAGACAAGAAAUAACUAAGAUCAGAGCAGAACUGAAGGAGAUAGAGACAUGAAAAACCCUUCAAAAAAUCAAUGAAUCCAGGAGUUGGUUUUUGGAAAAGAUCAACAAAAUAGAAAGAACACUAGCCAGACUAAUAAAGAAGAAAAGAGAGAAGAAUCAAAUAGACACAAUAAAAAAUUAUAAAGGGGAUAUCACCACUGUUCCCACAGAAAUACAAACUACCAUCAGAGAAUACUAUAAACACCUCCACACAAAUAAACUAGAAAACCUGGAAGAAAUGGUUAAAUUCCUGGAAACACACACCCUCCCAAGUCUAAUCCAGGAAGAAGUCAAAUCCAUGAAUAGACCAAAAACAAGUCCCAAAAUUGAGGCAGUAAUUAAUAGCCUACCAACAAAAAAUAGUCCAGGACCAGCCAAAUUCUACCAGACAUACAAAGAGGAGCUGGUACUAUUCCUUCUGAAACUAUUCCAAGCAAUAGAAAACGAGAGGCUCCUCCCUAACUCAUUUUAUGCGGCCAGCAUCAUCCUGAUAUGAAAACCUGGCAGAGACACAGCAAAAAAAGAACAUGCCAGGCCAAUAUCCCUGAUGAACAUGAUGCAAAAAUCCUCAAAAAAUACUGGCAAACUGAAUUCAGCGGCACAUCAAAAAGCUUAUCCACCAAUCAAAUUGGCUUUAUCCCUGGGAUGCAAGGCUGGCUUAACAUACGCAAAUCAAUAAACGUAACCCAUCUCAUAAACAGAACCAAUGACAAAAGCACAUGUUUAUCUCAACAGAUGCCGAAAAGGCCUUUGAUAAAAUUCAACACCCUUCGUGCUAAAAACUCUCAAUAAACUAGGUAUUGACAAACAUAUCUCCAAAUAAUAAGAGCUAUUAUGACAAACCCACAGCCAAUAUCAUACUGAAUGGGCAAAAACUGGACGCAUUCCCUUUGAAAACCGGCACAAAACAAUGAUGCCCUCUCUCACCACUCCUAUUCAACAUAGUAUUGAAAGUGCUGGCCAGGGCAAUCAGGCAAGAUAAAGAAAUAAAGGAUAUUCAAAUAGGAAAAGAGGAAGUCAAAUCGUCUCUGUUUGCAGAUGACAUGAUUGUAUAUUUAGAAAACCCCAUCGUCUCAGGCCAAAAUCUCCUUAAGCUGAUAAGCAACUUCAGCAAAAUGUCAGGAUACAAAAUCAAUGUGCAAAAAUCACAAGCAUUCCUAUACACCAAUAACAGACAAACAGAGCCAAAUCGAAUGAACUGCCAUUCACAAUUGCUACAAAAGAGUGUAAAAUACCUAGAAAUACAACUUACGAGGGAUAUGAAUGACCUCUUCAAGGAGAACUACAAAUUAGUGCUCAAGGAAAUAAGAGAGGACACAAACAAAUGGAAAAACAUUCCAUGCUCAUGGAUAUGAAGAAUCAAUAUCAUGAAAAUGGCCAUCUACUGCCCUAAGUAAUUUUUAGAUUCAAUACUAUCCCCGUCAAGCUAUCAUUGAAUUUCUUCACAGAAUUAGAAAAAAAAAAAAACUACUUUAAAUUUCAUGUGGAACCAGAAAACAGCCCAUGUAGCCCAGGCAAUCCUAAGCAAAAAGAACAAAGCUGGAGGCAUCAUGCUACCUGGCUUCAAACUAUACUACAAGGCUACAGUAAUAAAAACAGUAUGGUCCUGGUACCAAAGCAGAUAUAUAGACCAAUGGAACAGAAUAGAGGCCUCACAAAUAACACCACACAUCUACAACCAUCUGAUCUUUGACAAACCUGACAAAAACAAGCAAUGAGGAAAGGAUUCCCUAUUUAAUAAAUGGUGUUGGGAAAACUGGCUAGCCAUAUGCAGAAAGCAGAAACUGGACCCCUUCCUUAUAUCUUAUACAAAAAUUAACUCAAGAUGGAUUAAAGACUUAAACAUAAAACCAUCAACACGCUGAACCAUGCACUUGCCUUGCUAUUGAUGGC